UUCAGAAUCACGCCGGCCUCAUUCUACCGCUGCUCUCUCCUGGAUCUCGGCCACGGAUCUUUUGCUCGCGAAAGUUCCUCCGUCUAGCUGCACACAACGCUGCUGCAGGAAACCGAGGUAAGGGAUUUGCCGAGACUUAGCUCCACCACACUCCCCGAGGCCCCGCCCCUCCUCUCUGGCCCUCCCCUAGGCCCAGGUGUCUCGCGUUGCACGUGCAGUUGUUGUGGUUCUACGUCACGUGGUCCCGGAAGUUCAAGACAGACCCGCCUCAAACAUGGCGGCGCCCAGCGCGCGAGGACGUGAUCCGCUUCUGCUCCGGCUUGGAUUGUAGCCUUGACGAGGUCUGAGCGACCAUGGACCGGCCGGGGUUCGUGGCAGCGCUGGUGGCUGGUGGGGUAGCAGGUGUUUCUGUUGACUUGAUAUUAUUUCCUCUGGAUACCAUUAAAACCAGGCUGCAGAGUCCCCAAGGAUUUAGUAAGGCUGGUGGUUUUCAUGGAAUAUAUGCUGGCGUUCCUUCUGCUGCUAUUGGAUCCUUUCCUAAUGCUGCUGCAUUUUUUAUCACCUAUGAAUAUGUGAAGUGGUUUUUGCAUGCUGAUUCAUCUUCAUAUUUGACACCUAUGAAACAUAUGUUGGCUGCCUCUGCUGGAGAAGUGGUUGCCUGCCUGAUUCGAGUUCCAUCUGAAGUGGUUAAGCAGAGGGCACAGGUAUCUGCUUCUACAAGAACAUUUCAGAUUUUCUCUAACAUCUUAUAUGAAGAGGGUAUCCAAGGGUUGUAUCGAGGCUAUAAAAGCACAGUUUUAAGAGAGAUAAAUUCACUGAUAGAAUUUUUCAGUAAAUCCUAAGAAAAUAAUGUGAUGGGGGAUCUACAAGACUUGAACCAAAUCUUGACCUGAGUGAGAGUGGAGCACAAUUUCUGAGUGUUAGAGGAUUCUAAAGGAUAGAAAUGGAACUGUUUGUAUGGGCAGAACACAAUGAGAUGCUUCUAAAACAGCCAUUAAUAUUGAUUUCAGCAUCCUUUUUCGUCUGGCCUUUGUGAGGGGUGCUUAAAAAUGUUUUGACUGAUUGUAGUCUGUCCUUUUUUGUUCCCUGUGCUGCAUCAUAUGUUCUGAGAAACAGUAGAGUAGGUGGGAAAAGGUUGAUAAUCUUUGGCCUUGAAGUGGUUUUGGUAUACAUAGCCAAGUAACUAGCAGAUAAUUUAUUGACUAGUGGAGAAGCAGAAAUUUUUGUGAGGAUUUUUUUUUUUCCCUUUUUGAAUAUACUCUGCUUUUUGUUAUUCAACUUGUCAGUGCAAAACUGACAUUAUAGAAGAACGCACUAGAGGGCGCACAAUGCCUGUAUUUUAAAUGUUGGUGGCAAAAACCUCAGCAUGAACUUGGAAGCUGCUUCCUGGCACUGUUUGAAAAAAAAAAAAAAAGGUUCAAAUUAGAAAAUGUAAAUUUAAGCAUAAUAGUGUUUUCCGAUCAAGAUACCUGAAUGGAUAAAUUUGUGUUAUCUUUUGAUACAUAUGUACAUGGAGUUGUAUUUAUUUGGGUUCUAAUUUUUUAAAACUUUUACCAUGGAAAAAUUUAAAGACACACAAAAAAGAUUACUAAAAUGAAUCCCUGUAGUCUCAUCAAUUACCAGCUCUUGAGCAGUAUUGUUCCAUCUAUACCAAACCCUGCUUCCCACAUGUCUGUAUGAUAUUGAAGCAAAUACCAGACAUUCUGAUUUCAUCCAGAAAUACGUCACUAUGCAUCUCUAAAAGAUAACUGUAAAUAUGUAUAAUGUAUCAAAAAUGAGUGUCAUAACAGAAAGACAAAUAUUGUAUUAUAUGUGUAAACUAAGAAAGUAAAAUUCAUAGAAGCAGAGAGUAGAACCAUGGUUCUCGGGUGUUAGGGGGUGGGUAAAUGGGGAGAUGUUGUUCAAAGGGUACAAAUUGUCAGUUAUAGGAUCAGCAGGUUCUGGGUAUUUAAGGUACAGCAUGAAAAGUGAUGGAUGUGUUAAUUAAUUUGAUUGUGGUAAUCAUUACACAUUGUGUAUCAAAUCAUCACAUUGCUCACUUUAAUAUAUAUAAUCUUUAUUUGUCAUUUAUUUUAAAAAACGAAUAUCAUAGUCUAGAAGUAUUUCCCCAAAGCUAUUUAUCACUUACAAAGGGGAAAAUAGUAAUUUUACAGUUGGAAAGACUGGCAGUCACUAUUUUAUCCAAGUGAUCAAGAUUAGCAUCACCAGUAAUAAGAUUAUAUUAACAUCAUACAUCUCUAAUAUAAUGCACCAAGAAGGACACAAUGUCACUUCUUUGGUCUUCUUGCCAAAGAUGCAUAAUCUCAGUGUGAUCAUGAGAAAACAUCACACAAACCGAGAUUGAGAGACAUUGUACAGAAUUGUCAAAGUUAUGAUAAAGAAAGAUGAAAGAACUGCCACAAAUAAGAGAAGACUAAGGAGACACAACAAGUAAAUGCAGUGUAGGAUCCUGGAUUUGAUCCUGGAACAGAAAAGAUUUUGGGAAAAACUGGUAACAUUCAAAAUCUGUAAUUUAGCUAUUAGCAUUGCAGCAAAACUGGUAGCUGGUUUUGAUAAGUGUACUGUAGUUAAUUUAUUAACAUUAGAGAAGCCAGCAUAUAUGUGAACUCUGCUAUUUAUGCAACUUUUAUGAGAGUUUGUUUUUAAAAAACAAACUAAAAUGCCACAUUUGGACAUUGUAUGAAGUACUUGUUUUUAGAGUCAUCUUCUAAAAUAAUGACAAGUUAAAUUUAAAAUUUAAUUUCUUUUAUUGUUAACUUGUAUUAAAAUAAUAUAUGCAAUUAGUAACAACCCAAAUAAUGUAGAAGGACUUAAGAUGAAAAACAACAGUCUCCUGCCCAUCCCUCUCCAUUCUGGUUCCACUCUCUAGAGGUAGCCUUUAUUUUUUAUUUUUUAAAAUUUUAACUGUUUUAUUUUUAGUUCUUAUUUCAUCGGUGCUUUCAGAUAAUAUAUUAUUUAAAUGUCUGUUUUAAAAUUUGUCAGUAGAUAAAGUUUGUUGAGUCUUUGGGAUGGAAGAUGUGAUUAAGCUCACAUUAUGUUCUUCCCCAACCCUGUCUCAUCCUAGCAUUCCAGUUAUAUAAAUUUCAUUCCUCUGUUCAUUUUAGAAACUUUAAGUUAUAUAUUCGUUUCUUUAUUUCUUAUCCUACGAACUUUCUGCAUCUUACAACUUUCUCUUGACAUGAUGAGGCUGUUGCUUUCUUUUUGCCACCUUGUCCUCCUUAACCUGCAAAUUUCACUUUCUGGAAAGACUUCUCUCAACUAUACUUUCAUUGUACAUUGUCAAGAGGGUUGACAAUUUCAUCCUGUCUUUUACCCUCAGUCACUUCUUUCAUAGCUCUUCUGUAUUGAUUCUAAAAGUGGAGUACCGGUGAACUAGUGUUUGUAUUAUUGAGAAGACUUCAUGAAUGAUCAGACCAUGUAGUGUGCUAAGGCUGUAUUUUUUUUUGUGUGUGGGACUUACACCCUGAGAGAUGGUUUCAGCAUCAGAAUCAAAUAGACCUUCUUGCACUCUAUCAGUUGCUAAAAUUUAAUUUCCAACAUUUGGGGCAUGAGCUUGUCUUUUUUUCUUGGAGUUUCUAAUUGCCUUUUCUGUAUGAAAAAGGCAUUAUUUGCAUUAUUUUUAGGUAUGACAACUUUGAAAACAUACUGUCUUUUGUCCUGAGUCCCCUUUUACCCUGGGAAUCUUGGAAUCUUUCAUUCUCCUGUUCUAAUCCUGUGUUAAUAUUCACUGUGUUUGGGCUUCUAUUCUUGGGUCAGAUUUGCUGUUUCCUGAAGGCCGCAUAGCAUAGUGGUUCAGACCAGGGCUUUGUGGUCAGGCAGCCCAGGUUUUGCCAACAGCUCUGCCUCUGUUAAACUUACACCUGGUGCUACAGUGUCCUCAUUGAAUGAAAAUGCUUUCAGAUAUGAAAAAUAUAAGAAUUUAGUCCAUUUGUUUGAAGGCUUUUAUUUGAUUCUGAUUUUUUUGGGGAGGUGGGGUCAGGUAAUUAUCUUUCUCUAGUGCCUAUUAUUUUACAAAUAUCUCAUUAAAGACAGCCGAUGAUAACCAUUCUCAUGAUUCUUUGGCCUCAAAUGUGUUUCACUGGUUUGUUUUUUAUAGUAGGAAGGAAUUAUGUUAAUGUUAUGAUUCUUAGAAAAGUAUUUUGAUCUUAUUAGUUUAGUGUGUAUCCUGAUUAUGUUUUGGAAAUAAGUGGUUAAAUUGAUCUGUGGGAGUCUUACAAACUGAUUACCAAGUUUCUGAUACAGCUUGCCUGUGUCUUGAUCCACGUAUUGUAAGUCUUUCCUAUUAUCAGUGAAUUUUUCCAUACUUCUGUUUCAGAGAAUGGAAUGAUGACUAAGUUAAAAAUCACUUCGGGACAAAAUUUAUUAUCCUUCACAGGGUAAAUGACAAACAUGUCAUUUACCUGGUAGAGGAUACCAAUAGUAUCUGUGUUCACAGUCAGCUAUGCUAUGUUUCAUGUUGACUAACAAAGAUCUUGUGAUAAUUAGACUCUGCUGAUUUAUCUUUUUGUUCACACAAUGGUUUUCCAAGGUUUUCUCAUCCUUUUAGACAUUUAAUAUUAGUUUGAAAAAGUAGUGAGAACAACACAUCUCAAUCAUUAAGUUUUGAUGAAGUGAAGACACCAAAGGUCUGGUAUAUAGUUGCCUCUUGGUAAGUGAUAAGUUCUUACCACAUUAUUUUUCUGUAUUUGAAGGAGAAAGUAGGUUGAAUUUAUCCAGCAUCUGCCAUAUGCCAGAUGAGGUACUUUUCAUAUAUAUUUUUUUCAUUUAAUCUUCACAGUAAUUCUCAAUCAUUAUUGCCAACUGAGUAAUUGGAAAGUAAGUACCUCUUGAAUACCUUGUCAUGAUUCCCAGUCAAUCUGUAAUGUUCAUCUACCUUGUAAACCAUUUUAUAUGCUAACAGACAUUUCUCUGUUUAAUACCAGUGAGAAAGCUGACCUUUGGUGGUGUAACUUGAUCUACAUAAAGCACGAAACACUGUUAGUGGAAGGCAGAGUUGGUCUCUGAAUUCUUUGAACUCUUAACGCUCGUCUAGUAACAGCAUAUUUAUUUCCUUUCUACUCUUUGAGGUAUGAGUGAGGAAGUUUGAAAUGCAUAGUAACACCACCUUUUUCUUUUUUUUCUGCCUUUCCAGCUUUUUUGAAAAAUUACAAUUUAUAGAAAAGGUAAAACGUGUAUUUUUUUUCCCCAGGAUUCACCAGUUAACAUUUUGCUUAAUCUGCUCUGCUCCUCUUUCUUCCUCUUUUUUUUCCUGAAAUAUUUUAAGUAAGUAGCAGACAAUUUGACACUUAUCAUUUAGUAUUUCAGCAUGUCUCCUAAGAAUGGAGUCCUACUUCUCAUAACUACAAUGCCAUUAUCACACCCAAGAAAUUUAAUAUUCACUAACUAAUAUUAUCUAAUAUGUGGUCAAUUUCCCUGAUGUCCCAGUGAUAAAAGCCUUACAGCUUCUUUCUCUACUCAGGAUACAAGUGAACAAAUACAUUGCAUUUGGUUGUCAGGGUCCCCAACCUUUUUUAUUUCCUCCAUGACAUAGACUUUUGUAGAGUCCGAGAUAUUUAUCCUGUAAACGGUCCCAUAAUCUGGAUUAUCUGAGUUCCUUAUGAUUAGACUCAGGUUAAUUGGUUUUUUUAUAUGAAUACCUAAGUAUUUUGGGGUGUUUCUCAUUGAGUUAUACCAGGAGGCACAAAAAGUCUUACACUUGGUGAGUUUAAUGGUUUGAUUAAGUUGUUUUCGUUUGUUAUACACUAAAGGUUCAAUUAUCCUUUGAUGUUAAGAGGCAAUCUAUGCGGUAAUAUUUUGAGAACAAGUGAUUAUCCCAUUCCCCAAUAAAUAGUUUUAACAUCUGUG